AGUGCUUAGUGCAUCCAAGAAUGUUAAUGUUUACACUGCAUGGGCUCUGGCCGCGACAGUGGCACAUUGCAUCCUCUGCUGUGCUCCACCUCCGGGCUUCUGGUUACAAGUACUCUACACAAGCUUAAGUGUUCCCUGUGUUGGGCUCCUGCUAUGGGCCUGGGCAAGUUUCCACCUUUUCCCUGCCUCCUCCUCCUUCCACCUUUUCUCCCUUUUUCUAGAAAUAAAAUCCCAAUCUUAUGCUCAGAAAUAAAUAAAACUUUAUUGUCAAAUAAAAGAGGCAGGCCAAAUUGAGGACUAUGGUUCUGCCUUCAAGAUGUGUUUUGCAGACGCUCCAGGAGAUGUUAAUAUCCUGAGCACUGGAAAUAGCUUCCAAUAAUAGGCCCUAUGCUUGGUAACAUACUAUGAUAUUGGUCUACCGUAUUUUUUCCUUUGCAACUAUCAUUAUCUUCAGCACCAUUUUAUGAAAGAAACUAAACCAUUUUCAUGGGCUGCUAAGGGUGUCAUUGGGCUUAGUUACCUUACCUACUGUACCUAAUGGAUAAGUGCCCCUGCCUCAUAUUUCUGCAAGAUGGCUAAGAAAUCAGCUUAAAAAAAAGUGAUUAAACAAUUCACUUUUAAAAAGAUGUCAAGGGAUGGCAAUCUCACAACCUCUCUCUGACUUCAACCAAAAUCUGACUUUUGUUGGAGUCUGGCCCCCUCUCCUUCUCUUAACUAAUCAGUUCAUGAUCAAUUUUCAGCCUUGGAUCAAAUGCUGCAUGAGAGACAUGUAAGAGUUUUAAUCAUGGAGUGCAGUAGACUAGCUGGGACGUCUGUGACAGCUUGAUUUCUUCCACAUCUCAGAUUUCCACAGUGUACCCCGGUGUUUUCUCACCUUCAGUCACUCAUAGGCAUCUUAGGUGAGUGUUGUUGCCCUAUGUGGGCACCAGAAAAGCUAGUACUUACUUAAAUGUUUUACUUUAAAUAUAAUUUAAUUUUUAAUUUUUGAUUCACUCUUGAAAACCUUAAGUACCUAAUGGAACCCUCAUCCUAAGCAAAAAUAGCCACAAAUCACGGCCUGAUGUAACAGAUUUAUGUGAGCAGUGACCCUAGAACCAGACUAGGUAUCUGAAUCAUGGCUUCACUCACUACUUGCUAGCUGGCUAAUCUGGUGAGCAGUUUAUUCUCAUUUUGCCUUGGUUUAAUAAUUUUUUAAAUGGAGAUAACAAUCAUACCUAAUUCAUAGAGGUGUUUUGAGGAUUAAUUGAGGUGCUUAAUUAUACAAUUUCACAAAUGACCAUGCAGCCUCACAUUUCCUACUUGACUCACUUUCAUAUUUUUUUAUUCACAAGGGAGAGAGAGUGAUUGUUCUCCUCUGGCAGCAUGUAAUAAAGAUAGAGCAUCUUCUUGUGAAAACAAUACACGUACCAUGUUUCUAUGUACCUAUAUGUGCUUCCAUCAAUAAGCCUAUGUUGGUUGCUGCAUGUAUGAGCCCUGGGCCAGGAAAUGUGCCAGGAGAGUGUGUCUUUCACUCAGCAGACAGAUUUUCUUCCUUGGCCUAAUAUAUCUUAUUCCUAGAUACCAGAGCAAAUAAUAAUGUAAUAAGCAUUACCAUGUAUUAAGUACCUACUCUGGACCCAACCCAAGAACAAGCAGUAUGAAGGUGAUAAGCAGGGGCACCAUGGUGUAAUUCACAUUUUCAUCAUCAGAUCACUCUGGCUGCUGGGUGGAGAAUGUUUAUAGGAGAAAAAAGGUGAAAGCAGGGAGACAGGACACUAAUGCAAUAUCCCAGGUUUAAGAUGAUAGAGAUUAUCUUAAGCAUGUCAGAGAAAAAAAAUUAAAGGUUUGGGAAUGUGUUUCUGAGGCGGAGUCAACAGGAUUUGCUGAUAAAUUGACUAUUUGGAGUUGAAGAAAAAGAAUAAAACAGUCUAUAUAUAACCAAGUACCUCUUUUUUAAAGAAUCAAAUGAAUUAUUUUUUCCUUUUUCCUUUCCUCACACCUCCUACUUAGCUCUUUGGGAAUGCAAUUAUAAACUUUACCUUCUCUCCACCAGACACUCCCUACACAGCAAGCUUAUCUAACUACAUGUUUACUUAGAAGUUACAGAGACCGAACCUUAAAGCAAACCAGGAACCUCCAGAACUCUCUCCUACCAGGAGGCAAAUUGAGAUUGCCUCAACUUACAACCUAGCUCUGCCCGUGACGGUGCCAGCCAGACCACCUGAUAGAUAAGACAUCCGAAGCAAGUCACAUAGACUCUGCACUUCAUCGCCCUCUCCCCUGCAUGCCAUUCACGCCAAGCCCCACUUUCAAAGCUCCUGCCUUCUGCCCCAAAGGCUUUAGUGGCUUCCUCAAGGCAGCCUGUACUACUUCCCCUCAACUAGCUCUGGAAUAAAGCCACUUUCUUUCUACCAGACGUCGUUCUUGUUCACUGGACUUUGCAACUGGUGAGCAGUCGGAGCUGUGUUCAGUUACAUGUAUGCCUUGCCUCAUUGAACUCUCAUGAAAACCCUAUGAUCGAGACACUGUUGUUAUCUCCAUUUUAUAGGUGAGGAAGCUGAGAACCAGAUAGAUUCAUCCAGUGUCCUAGGACACACAGUGAGUCAUGCUUCGGAUCUGUGCUCCUAGCUGAUGCCUCCCAUUACUGGUAGUCCUUUCCUGCUCCCCACAAUGUACAUUUAUUCAUUUCUUUUUCUAUUUUCUUAUUAUCUUUCUAUUUUUCUUCUUCUUCCUCUCUCUUCUCUCACUAGGGAUAGAACGCAAGGAUCUCACUUAGCCCAGUGGAUGGCAGUCAAUUAAUGGAGCGAGUGGCUUAGUCCUUGUCAUGCUGCCAAGUGCAAGGGCCUUUCCAUGCUCAGAAUCACCAUGAAGACGAGAGCUAUCUCUCUUGCUGCAGACGCCACGGAGUUUGUGCAGGGGCGCAGCGCUCCAGCCAUGGCGCGUUCGCUCGUCCACGACACCGUGUUCUACUGCCUGAGUGUAUACCAGGUAAAAAUAAGCCCCACACCUCAGCUGGGGGCAGCAUCAAGCGCAGAAGGCCAUGUUGGCCAAGGAGCUCCAGGCCUCAUGGGUAAUAUGAACCCUGAGGGCGGUGUGAACCACGAGAACGGCAUGAACCGCGAUGGCGGCAUGAUCCCCGAGGGCGGCGGUGGAAACCAGGAGCCUCGGCAGCAGCCGCAGCCCCCGCCGGAGGAGCCGGCCCAGGCGGCCAUGGAGGGUCCGCAGCCCGAGAACAUGCAGCCACGAACUCGGCGCACGAAGUUCACGCUGUUGCAGGUGGAGGAGCUGGAAAGUGUUUUCCGACACACUCAAUACCCUGAUGUGCCCACAAGAAGGGAACUUGCCGAAAACUUAGGUGUGACUGAAGACAAAGUGCGGGUUUGGUUUAAGAAUAAAAGGGCCAGAUGUAGGCGACAUCAGAGAGAAUUAAUGCUCGCCAAUGAACUACGUGCUGACCCAGACGACUGUGUCUACAUCGUCGUGGACUAGCCCUAGAAUGCCAUCCUUCUUCAGGAGCUAGUUUGGAGAUGGGUUUUUCUGGUGCCACUGACACCUGGGCUGCCCAUGCCGCUCAGGCUACCCUUAUCUCCUCUGCACUUAUGUUAUCAAUAAAGAGGCAAAUUCUCAAUA